GUUCACUGAGGGGGCAGUGAGACGUGGGGCUGCUGGUCCUAGGAGCUCUUCCAUGACACCUAGUGUUACCUGGGAGCCCCAAGCCCCAGUCCCCCAUCCCUCAGGAAAUCCAGUUGGAACCCCUACUUUGCAGGGCCAUCUUUGGCCUGAAGCCACCAGGAAAGCUGUCCCACUGACUGACCCCUCUUAAGGAAGCUGCAGACUGCUGGGCCCAUUUUCAGAUAGAGGAACGGAGAGCUGCGGCAGCCCAGGAGCCCUGCCAGGCUUCCUUCUGGGUGCAGCCACCUGUGGGUGGGGCGCGGCCUCGUCUGAGACCAAGGCAGGGCCCAUGCCUUACUCAGCUGUCCUUGCUAAGAGUCCCCUAGCAUCUUCCUGAUGGUCUUUCUGCCUUGGGGUGAAGAGGCAUUUGGGGGAAUUGCCAUCUUGGGAGGAAAAGCAGUAUCCUUUCACUUUCAGACUGAAAGGCUCCUGGGGAACUUGCUUCACUCCGGCGCUUUCUGUCCCAUGCUGAAGGCUGGAGUCGCCAGCCCCUUCCCCUUUGCCUUUCUCAGGCCCCAGUCCCUGAGGUGUGUGUGAGGACUGAACUUUAAUCCGGAACAAUCUGGUUUCUCCUCGGUCAGCCCAGCCGGUGCUUCCCCCGCCCCCACCCACGCUGCAAGAGGCGAGGGAGGGGUGGUGACUCAGUGUGCAUGUGUACAUCUGUCCCUGUGGUCCCGGCAGCUCGCCGGGUGGGGCAGGAACCAGAAGUCUCGCGGCACCUUUCCCCCACCCCCAGCCAUGGGAACAAGGAGGUCUUCUCCUGCCGGGGCAUCCUGCUGGCAGUGAACUGGUUUCUGGAGCGGGGCCACACAGACAUCACAGUGUUUGUGCCAUCCUGGAGGAAGGAGCAGCCUCGGCCCGACGUGCCCAUCACAGACCAGCACAUCCUGCGGGAACUGGAGAAGAAGAAGAUCCUGGUGUUCACACCAUCACGACGCGUGGGUGGCAAGCGGGUGGUGUGCUAUGACGACAGAUUCAUUGUGAAGCUGGCCUACGAGUCUGACGGGAUCGUGGUUUCCAACGACACAUACCGUGACCUCCAAGGCGAGCGGCAGGAGUGGAAGCGCUUCAUCGAGGAGCGGCUGCUCAUGUACUCCUUCGUCAAUGACAAGUUUAUGCCCCCUGAUGACCCACUGGGCCGGCACGGGCCCAGCCUGGACAACUUCCUGCGUAAGAAGCCACUCACUUUGGAGCACAGGAAGCAGCCGUGUCCCUAUGGAAGGAAAUGCACCUAUGGGAUCAAGUGCCGAUUCUUCCACCCAGAGCGGCCAAGCUGCCCCCAGCGCUCUGUGGCAGAUGAGCUCCGUGCCAAUGCUCUCCUCUCACCCCCCAGAGCCCCAAGCAAGGACAAAAAUGGCCGGCGGCCUUCACCUUCAUCCCAGUCCAGCUCUCUGCUAACAGAGAGUGAGCAGUGCAGCCUGGAUGGGAAGAAGCUGGGGGCCCAGGCAUCCCCAGGGUCCCGCCAAGAGGGUCUAACACAGACCUAUGCCCCAUCAGGCAGGAGCCUCGCACCUAGCGGGGGCAGUGGCAGCAGCUUUGGGCCCACAGACUGGCUCCCACAGACGCUGGACUCACUCCCGUACGUCUCCCAGGAUUGCCUGGACUCGGGCAUUGGCUCCCUGGAGAGCCAGAUGUCGGAACUUUGGGGGGUUCGAGGAGGAGGCCCUGGUGAGCCGGGCCCACCCCGAGCCCCUUACACGGGCUACAGUCCCUAUGGAUCUGAGCUCCCAGCCACCGCAGCCUUCUCUGCCUUUGGCCGGGCCAUGGGUGCUGGCCACUUCAGUGUCCCUGCCGACUACCCACCCGCGCCCCCUGCCUUUCCACCUCGAGAGUACUGGUCUGAACCAUACCCACUGCCCCCACCCACAUCAGUCCUUCAGGAGCCCCCAGUGCAGAGCCCAGGGGCUGGCAGGAGCCCGUGGGGCAGGGCAGGCAGCCUGGCCAAGGAGCAGGCCAGCGUGUAUACUAAGCUGUGUGGUGUGUUUCCCCCGCACCUGGUGGAGGCUGUGAUGGGGCGCUUCCCACAGCUCCUGGACCCCCAGCAGCUGGCUGCCGAGAUCCUCUCCUACAAGUCCCAGCACCCCAGUGAGUAAGCUGCCUGUGGCUGGCAAGGGCAGCACCCCCAGCCUCCAAGGGCCGUCAGGCUGGGCUUUGGGCCAUUGAGCAGCCCAUUCCCAGCCCUGAGGCCCACCCCAGAGGCUGGACAGAGGGAGGAUUCAAGUCGGGAAGGAAACCCACAAACCAAAGAUACUGUAGGAUUGGUUCUGGCCCAUGCAGCACCUCUAGCUGUCUGCCUCAGUGGGUCAGAAGCGAUCACCCUGUUGAUACACAUUGUAUCUCUGUAGUUUAAGGAGACGCUGCCGGUAACGGCGUCGGUCCGUGGCUGAGGCCCAAACCGUCUUUUCUCUCAGAGGGUGGGGAGGGAGGUGGGGGCAGCAGAGGCCUGGGCUGGGUGCCCUGUGCACGCCACCCCACUUCCGCCCUACCCCUGGGACGUUGGCCUUGGCUGGCUAGUUGGGCACCGUGUGCCUGCCCUCCAAGGGCCUCCUCUACGCCAAUGAGGCCUCAUCUGUGCUCUCGCUGGGCACGUGGCUUCAUGUCAGUAAGCAAGAUGCUUCUUAAUAACCCACCUUCUGCCCCACUCUAUUCCUUAUCCUGCUGCCCCUGUAGGGGUCAAGGGCCCUCCGUCUACACCCUCUUCUUCUCCUCCAUCCUUUAUUCAGAGUCAUCUCGCCCUUCCCCAUGGGUGGGGGAACCUGUGUUUGUUUGUGUGCACAUGUAAAUUUUAAAUAUUUUAAGCAGAAAGUCCUUACCUCCUGUAACACAUCAAUAAAGUACAAUCAUUGUGAGCCCUUUCAA